CUUUUUUUCAGGCGGCCGGGAAGAUGGCGGACAUUCAGACUGAGCGUGCCUACCAAAAGCAGCCGACCAUCUUUCAAAACAAGAAGAGGGUCCUGCUGGGAGAAACUGGCAAGGAGAAGCUCCCGCGGUACUACAAGAACAUCGGUCUGGGCUUCAAGACACCCAAGGAGGCUAUUGAGGGCACCUACAUUGACAAGAAAUGCCCCUUCACUGGUAAUGUGUCCAUUCGAGGGCGGAUCCUCUCUGGCGUGGUGACCAAGAUGAAGAUGCAGAGGACCAUUGUCAUCCGCCGAGACUAUCUGCACUACAUCCGCAAGUACAACCGCUUCGAGAAGCGCCACAAGAACAUGUCUGUACACCUGUCCCCCUGCUUCAGGGACGUCCAGAUCGGUGACAUCGUCACAGUGGGCGAGUGCCGGCCUCUGAGCAAGACAGUGCGCUUCAACGUGCUCAAGGUCACCAAGGCUGCCGGCACCAAGAAGCAGUUCCAGAAGUUCUGAGGCUGGACAUCGGCCCGCUCCCCACAAUGAAAUAAAGUUAUUUUCUCAUUCCCAGGCCAGACUUGGGAUCUUC